ACACCGGGGGCUCUCGGGCACCCGCGCGGCGCCGGUUGGCCUUCCCGGCGCUCGCCCGGGGGCGCGCUUGCGCGCCAGCGGCUGCGGACACCAGCCUGCGUCCCCGGCGCGGCGGGCCAUGGAGGCCCUGAGGAGGGCCCACGAGGUCGCGCUCCGCCUGCUGCUGUGUAGGCCGUGGGCCUCGCGCGCCGCCGCCCGCCCCAAGCCCAGCGCCUCGGAGGUGCUGACGCGGCAUCUGCUGCAGCGGCGCCUGCCGCACUGGACCUCCUUCUGCGUGCCCUACAGCGCCGUCCGCAACGACCAGUUCGGCCUCUCGCACUUCAACUGGCCGGUGCAGGGCGCCAACUACCACGUCCUGCGCACCGGCUGCUUCCCCUUCAUCAAGUACCACUGCUCCAAGGCUCCCUGGCAGGACCUGGCCCGGCAGAACCGCUUCUUCACGGCGCUCAAGGUCGUCAACCUCGGUAUUCCAACUUUAUUAUAUGGACUUGGCUCCUGGUUAUUUGCCAGAGUCACAGAGACUGUGCAUACCAGUUAUGGACCCAUAACAGUUUAUUUUCUCAAUAAAGAAGAUGAAGGUGCCAUGUAUUGAAAGUGUGCGUCAAAGAACAUAAAUAUCAGUGGAUUUUCUCUGUGUAUAUGUGCAGUAUUUAUUUUUGAUCCUUUAAAAUAAAACUUUUGCAAAUACUUUUUUCUUUCUACAGUAUCUGCUUCUUUAAGAUGAAUCAUUGCCCUCAAGAGGUGAAGCUUUUUAUACAUCGUUAUAUAUUACAUACUCUGUUUAGCUGAUGUGAACUACAAACACAUGAAGCUUCACACCAUUUUUUCCCUAGAACUAGGUUAACCUACAGAUAAAAAAUGAUUACAAUGUAAUAGAUUCUAUAGUUAAUUAACAAUUUAAAUCAACUCUGAAGAGAAAAUAUAGAUGCCCACACAAAAGAGAAGGGGGGAAAAUCUUUUAUGUAACAAUGGAAAAAGAAGUAGAAGACAUUAGGAUGUAUGAUGGAAAUAUUACAUCAUUGGCAAAUCCAAAAUUGAUGAGAAUCUAAUUGUAAUCUCAAGUCUAAACCAUUCAGCUGCCAGGAUUGUAAAUAGAAACGUUUUAAAGGCCUUGUGCCAUUUACCUGGAGGAGGGGUUGGAGUGUAAUGUUGAAACUUCUUGUUGCUUAAAGAGUCCAAAACCAUAUCGUUUGUAAAAUGUAAUAAUAACUGGUUAAUAUAAGUGUAGCAAGGUGAAUGAAACUCAGACUUAUUAAAAGUUAAAACAGCUUUCCUAUAAAGCUGUAAGAACAAUUAAGAUCUUCUAGAAAGAUGCAGAAAAAUAAAUUUGGUAACUGUUUAUAAAAGCAAUUAACUGAAAUGGUACAUAUCCAUAGACUUAUUGGCAAUAAGGAGUGGGCUGAAAUUUUAAAGACCUAAUGGCACUUUUGCAUUUGAAUUUUAUUAACUUAAUUGCAUUUUUGAAAGCCAAGUCAUUUAAAAAAAUGUAUCCUUGGGGUAGUCACAAAAUACCCAGAUGAAUGGUAAAUUUCAGACAUUUGGAGUAAUUUAGGGAGAACUAAGUAGAACUAUUUAAUUUCUAAACCAAUGGGUGUUUAAGAUUUAUGAUCUCUCCCAUAAUUACAAACAUACAUUAUAUAUCAUUUUAUGUUAAUGUGUUGCUGAUACUCUGCAACACUUACACAUUUUUGUAGCAAAACAUUUUAUAAAAUUCAACAUUUGGAUGCUUAUGUCAAGUCAGUAGAGAAAGUGAGUGGAAGUGACUGAGGUGAAGGCACCAGAAUAAUGAAGUAAUACAAACUAGCUUCGUUAAAGGUAGUCAUUUUAAAUGAUCUACAGAGUGAACUGUUCUUCAAAUAUAUGUGGUGUUCACUUGUCUAAAAGCAAUUCUAAGUAACACUUUAAUCAAAGAAGUACUUAUGCCAAUAUAUUUAGUCCAGAAGAAUAUACUUGACACUAGUUAAAUGAAUGGCUUACACAAAGGAGAUAGUGUUACAUUAAGCUUCAUUAAUAAUAAAACAACUGGCUAUUAGCAUUUUGCAGGGAAGGCUAGAACUGAUUUCCUCUGUAAUGGGCAAAGUUAAAUAACUAUAGCUCAUAAGUUUUAAGUCAAAUACUGCUCAUUCAUUGCUGCUGGUCUUGUCAAUAGUGGCUGUAAAGGUUUGGUCCCAACACAAGGCUGAUAAAAUGGUCUUUAAUUACCAGACUAUAAAUACAGCUUUUCAGUAGAGUUGCACCUCUUUUCACACUGGCCUGUUUGAUUUCUGAUAAUUUGUACUGCUGACUCUGCUUACCUGUUUUUCAAUAGCUAUAGUCAGUGUGACUUCUUGCCCAUAUGUGAUAGGUAAGUGUCCUUGGAGAACAUCUUUGACAAACUACCCUAUUGAUCUCUGUAAUUCUCUGCUGCUUGCAGCAUUAAACAGGGCCUUGAUUUCUUGUCUGAUGUGCUCACUGUAUAACAAGUAAAUGUAAUAUUUUCUUGUAUUACAUGAAAAUCAAUAGACCUCUUGCUCUUACGGAGUUGAUCAUGGUGAAGGAUGAACUAACUCAACAAUGGGUAAAGGCGUGGUUUAAAAAUUUAAAUAUCAUUCAUUGGAUUUAUUAAGUCUUGUAAACUUGUAGUCUGAAAACAAUACUUCCCAUUGAACAGCAAUGGUUUAAGUUUUUUCUUUAAAGCUGCAUAUUACACCAAAGUAUUAUGGCCUGAAAGGGAGAAAGUAUAAAUGUGUAAGUCAGGAGACUGAGUCUAUUUUUAGUAUUGGUGCUGUCUUACUUUUUGACCUCAGGCUAAUAACUCUCCUCCUUUGUGUCUUGGUUUUUCCACCUGUAAUCUGAGAAGAACGAAACAAGAGACAUUUCUACCCGAAAAUGUACAUCAAUUUUACUUUUGUCUCUGCAAAAGCUCUGUUUUUAUAAUCCACAUUCUUCUGCUCCAUUAUACUUAAAGGACUUCAUUAAUUAAAAAAUUUCAAAAAUAAGGUGAUGGAGAAAGAAGGAGAGAUGCAUUGAUAGCACAUGCCCACUAACCCUGAAGUGGCAUGUGGGGAGCUGAAGAGGCCCUUCUCUUCUGCAUAUCAGUAGUUUUCUUAAUUGGUGAAACCACUGAUUAGCUUUUCUGUCAUAUUUCUUUGACAGGAUUUUUAUCUUUAAUCCAACCAAAACUGUUUUAAUAAAGGUGUACUUUUAGUACAAAACCUUGCAUCUCUUCUAUUGUUAUUUCUAUACAAAUGAAUUAUCACGUAUUGGAAUAAAUUUCUAGGCAAAUUCCUAGGCAAAAUUCUUAGUUCCUGUGUAAGUUGUGAGCCACUAUAAAGAUGCAGUAACCUAUUUGGGAGCGUGAGAGAGGCUGCUAAUACAAAAAUCUCUAUUUUCUUAGUGUUGAUGUCCUAAAAUGCCAAAUUGUAGAAACAGUUAUAGUUUACCACACAUUUUGGGGCAUUAAUAUUUUUCUAACGUUGACUUCCGUAAAAAUUCAAACUUUUCUUUUUGAGAAGGAGUUUCAGUCUUGUUGUCUAGGCUGGAGUGCAAUGGUGCGACCUUGGCUCACUGCAACCUCCACCUCCCAGGUCCAAGCGAUUCUCCUGUCUCAGCCUCCUGAGUAGCUGGGAUUACAGGUAUGCACCACCACGCCGGCUAAUUUUGUAUUUUCUGUACAGACGGUUUCACCAUGUUGGUCAGGCUGGUCUUGAACUCCUGAUCUCAGGUGAUCUGCCGGCCUCGGCCUCCCAAAGUGCUGGGAUUACAGGCAUGAGCCACCAGGCCUAGCUGAAACAUUUGUAAUUAUUAAAACCGUGUAUCUUUUAAAGUACAUUUUACUUCAUGUCAUUUAUAUUCACCCAAAACUGUAAGCAUAGAACAUCUAUAGUUCUUCAUGAAAUAUCUUUUAACUCUGUUAAAGAAUGAUGUUUGAAUAAGUGGGAUGACAUAAAAGGCAAAGAUCUUGGUUUCACUGCACUGAAAAGCUAAUGCAGAUAACAGAAACCUUAUCCUAAAGCUAGUGGAUUAAGUAUCUACUGUUACUCAAACAAUAAUGACAUUUGGGGGCAUCUUAACCUAAACAAGUACUUAGCAUUACAUCUCACCUGGGUCAACAGUCUAGAGUAUCAGAGUUAAACUCUGUUACUGUAAAUUAAUGGAAAAUGUAACUGCACUUUGCUGAAAGAUCAAUGUCCAAUAAAGGCUGCACGAUCAAA